AUCUUGUGUCGGCGGCUCGGCUGUAAGGAGGUGGCAGGGACAACCACAACCACAACGGCCGGGGGAGGAGAAGGCGGCAGCGGCGAUUCUAGGCGGCCCAGGCGGCGGGGAGGAGGAGAAGGAGGAGGGUGGCGGCCGGGCUUGGCUUCGGCUCCUUGAGGAGUUGGCGGCGGCGCGACCCGGGGAACCGGCAUUGGUAAAAAAACGUCCUUUCACUGCGCCUCGCCCUGGGCAGGGGUUUCGGGGAGGCACUGGAGGGCCCUGAGCCACGCUGCUGUCGGGGCGGGCCGCGGUGACUCGGGAGCCAGGAAUCAGCGGAGUAGGGAGGGGGAGCGGAUCCUGGGGCGGGGCCGACUUUCCCCGGCCAGGACCACUCCGGCUCCCUCUGGUUGCAAAAUCUGACCUUGGAGUCGGACCCCCAGGAUGUGCUUUUAGAGACUCACGCCCAACAUCUCUAGUCUGGGACCUGACUCCGUCCCGAACCUUGUAUCUCAGAUCAGAACUCUUCCCCAGUCUCCAAUAGAGAUUUACGUGGAUCAGCAUUGCUGAUCAGAGCUCCUCACCAUUGAAUGCCGUUAAAGACCUGCCCCAGAAUCUCCUUUGAGACACUUCCUAGCUUCUCAGUAUUUGUCCUCAAGGCUUCCAGGACGGGCUAGAUCUCGAAGGGGUCCAUAGGCCCUUUAUCUCUGUAAGAGAGUCCUCUUUAGCAUUUUCCUUCAGACCCCCAUCCCACACACAUGCUAGCCGCGCUCAGAGCUUCCAGGGGUACUAGACCCUGUGAAAGGCCAUUUGGGCCUGGCCUUUGUGUCGGGGGCCCCUCUUCGCCACACGUCAGGUCUCCUAACCCCACCCUGGCCCUAGCAUCUUCCAUCAGAGACUCUGCCCAGUAUUUCUACUCAGAGACCCCUCUUACCAUCUGCCUUGAGAGACUCUUCAAUUCCUAGACUCUGUCCUUUGACACUUUCUCUACUUUUAUGGAAUUUCUCGCUUUUUAUACUUCCAGUAUUCAGAGACUACUGAGAGGCCUCAGCAUCUUCCCCAUCAGGCACCUUGAACCCCCAGAGCCUUCCAGUGCACCAGAUACCAGGGAGGAACUGUUUGGAUACAUAAUCCUCCAUCAAAGAGCCCCUGCGAGCAUCUGCUCUUGCAGAUCCCGUUGGCUUCUAGCCCCUUCCAUCAGAGACUCGCCUCCCCAACCCCACCCUAGACCCAGCCUCUGCCUUCAAAAACCAACCUGGGUUCUAGCUGCUUUUUUCACAGAUCCCUUAUCCUCACAUCAGGCCUCAGAAUCUGCCCUCAGAUCGUUUCAAGGUCCCUAACGUCUGCAGUCAGGGGUUUUCAGCUUCUGCUUUCAGCCUCCUUGGACCCCAGGAUCAUUGUCAGAUGUCCCUUCCCCCCACAGGCCUUCUUGUUUUCUUUUUCUUUUUCUUUUUUCCGAGACAGAAUUGUUUCACUAUGUCGUCCAGGCUGGAGUGCAGUGGCGCCAUCUCAGCUCACUGCAACCUCCACCUCCUGGGUUCAAGCGAUUCUCCUGCCUCAGCCUCCCGAGUAGCUGGGAUUACAGGCAUGCACCACCACGCCUGGCUAAUUUUUUGUAUUUUUAGUAGAGAUGGGGUUUCACCAUAUUGCCCAGGCUGGUCUCGAACUCCUGACCUCAGGUGAUCCACCUGCCUCGGCCUCCCAAAGUGCUGGGAUUGCAGGCGUGAGCCACCGCGCCUGGCCAUGGCCCUCUUGUUUUCUACUGCAGUAGAAAACCCUCUUCUCAGCAUCUACCUUCAGCGCCUCCAUGGGGUCCUACAUAAUUGGUCAGAGAAACCCAACCCCAUUUGGGGACCUAGCCAGUGUUUGCUUAUUAACCUUUUUAAGGCCUGCACUAUCUGGGCCCAGCUUCCCGUUUCCACACCCUCAGAGCAGCUGUGAUACCUAGCAUGUCCUGUCAGAGAUUGACACAGGGCCUUUGUGUUCCAUUAGAAACCUCUCCCAGCCCCUCACCAUCCACCCUCACAGCCUCCUGGGACUCUGUAGUAGGAAUGUCAGAUACACCUCUCCUCUUGCAUGUCCCUAUCUAUUAUUUUUGGUUAAAGAUUUCUCUCUGCUACCAGCAUCUGUCUCCAGAGUCCUCCAGAGCCUCAACAUCCUCCUGAUGGAGGCUGCCUCUCCCCCCAGACCCCAACAUCUUCCUGCUGCCUCCUCAGACUCUAGAAUCCCCCACCCAUUCCCUUUGCAGCUUCCAUGGGGCCCAGCAACUGUCCUCCUACCUCCUUGCAGCCUUGGGGGCCUCCACUGCAAUUUUUCAGCCUUUCUCCAAAAGAUCCUUUUCCAGAGAUCCGAAUUUGAGUCUUUUCCUAAUACCCUAGCCUAGUCCUUUCCCUCCCAGGACUUCUAACAUCUCCUUUCCCAUUUGUCUCAGAGCCUCCUUGCUCUUAGACACCCACUUCCUGAUUCUCCUCUCACGUUCCCAUGGACUUCUCAGUUAACCCCUCCCAGAAAGCUUGACAUGCUCCAGCCCCCCUUCUCUAUGCCCUAGCUUCUCCAUCCUGCUAACCUGCCUCCUCUCACACCUCCAAGACUCCUCCCUCAAACCCUCUGGUUUGGGAAUAGAGAAUGCUUACGCUUGAAAAUCUUCAGUUUGGAGACUCAGGUAUGUUUAGAAACUAAGCCACAGCUCAGCUUUGCCAAACAGUUCACAGUGUGUAUGUUAUGGUGGGGGCCUGAGCAAAUGUUGAGGUAGGAAGGGUGUAGAUUGUUUUUCUGCUGGGGGUGGGGGAUCUUUAGCUCCUCUGCAGAGUUUCUGUCCCAGACUCCUGCUUGCCUUGAGACAGGGCUGUUCCAAACCUUUGCAGUCAAAAUCCACUUGAACAAUCAUCUGAAACUUCUUAGACUCUUGCUGCCUGCACUGGGGAUCCAGAGGUGAAAUGUCCAGAUAUUAAAGUGCUCUCUGGCCCUGGAUCAUCUCUAAUUUAUGGAGUGAGGAAAUGGCAUGUCCCAAACAAACUGACCAAUGACAAGGCAAGGAGAUAACUAAGUAAUAGAGGCCACUACACGUGCCCAGGGAGGAACUCACAUCCUCAGGUCAGUGAGUUCUGACCACAGACCUUGGCUUCUUUAACCCUGCCAGCAGCCCCUUGAAGACAGUUUCAUUUGUCCCAGCUUUUGGAGAAAAUGAGGCUCAGAGGAAAUGAGAUCUCUACCCCAGGUCAGUCAGAGAGUCAGUAAAUGGAAAAUAUGGUUCACCUUUGUCUCUACUAACUCACCAAGCCUCUUGCUACCCAGGUUGGCUCUUAGCAUUCUAAGCAAUUCACCUGGCUAUCUCAGGGGCUCCAGCCAGCCUGCUGCCUCCCCUCAUCUCCCAUUCCUUAGCCCUGUGGACUGGGCCCUGAGCCCAGGGGCAUUUGGCAAACAGUCCCCCACCAGCUGCAUGCCUCUGGGCGAGUGAAUGGGGUUCUCUAAGCCUUUCUUUUCCCAUUUGUGAUUUGGGCAUAGGGUUAUCUGGGUCAUGGGGAUUGUUAAGAUUAGACAAAGCCCUUUCCUCUUUGAUUGACACACAGUAUGCUCUUGGUAGAUAGUAGGGAGCUCUUGUCAUUGUGGUUGGUGCUAGUGACAAGUGCCAAGAUGGAAUCUUAGGUACAUUGGGAUACUUAGUGUCAUAAAAGUCUCAGUGUGGGAGGACUUGUGUGAACAGAAGACUCAGUGCCUAGAGGAGCACUUGGGGUGAGGGGAAGUGACGCUGGGUCCUCCCAUCUCCAGCAUGUGGACCCAGUCACCCCCACCACCAGAUUUCACUUCCACAGCAGGCUUUAUUGUUCUGUCUCUGGGACCUAGCAGGUGACCCUGGGCAAGUUACUUCUCAUUUGUCCGGCAAGGACACUAAACUCUGCCUUGCUGGGUCAGGGUCAUGGAGGGGAUGAAACGUGAUAACACGAGGAAGCAGCCUGGGCUUCAGAGUCAGCAGAUCCUGGUCUGGUCCCAGCUCAGUGUGUGGGAACCUUGGUCACCGAACGUCCCUGAGUGAAUUUUUUUCCAUCACUUUAAAGUUGGGGGUAUUAUUGAUAGCAGUCCAAACCCCACAGGAGUACCCUGAGGACAGAGUGAGACGAGGUUUAGAGAAGUGCUUACUAUGGCAUCUGGCACAAGGAGGACUCCUGAUCAAUCUAAUACUCAUUUAUCAUUGUGGUUAACCUGUUUAAGGGACUCCGCAUGCAGAUGAGGCUUGGGAUGUGUUUGUUUUCUAUCUUUUUGCAACCUCUUUUAUUGGUCUGUGUCGGUUUUCCCCUCCCAAAGCUGGGGGCAGGGUUGGGCUUUAUAAAACUUGAGCCCCUCUGGGGACUGGGUUCUCAGCAAGUUACCGCUCCUGCCAUCAUGCCACCCUGAUGGAUGUCCAAGCCUCACUUCCCUCCUGCACUCCCCGCUCCCGCCGCCAUCCCUGGGAUUAAGGGAGAGGAGAAUGGCUGCUUGUUACUGCCUACCUACUCUGUGCCAGGUUCUAUGCUCUGUGUUAUUUAUCAUCUCGAUAACCCCGUGGGGAAGAUGUCCAGCUCGCCGCUGUCCAAGAAACGUCGCGUGUCCGGGCCUGAUCCAAAGCCGGGUUCUAACUGCUCCCCUGCCCAGUCCGUGUUGUCCGAAGUGCCCUCGGUGCCAACCAACGGAAUGGCCAAGAACGGCAGUGAAGCAGACAUAGACGAGGGCCUUUACUCCCGGCAGCUGUAUGUGUUGGGCCAUGAGGCAAUGAAGCGGCUCCAGACAUCCAGUGUCCUGGUAUCAGGCCUGCGGGGCCUGGGCGUGGAGAUCGCUAAGAACAUCAUCCUUGGUGGGGUCAAGGCUGUUACCCUACAUGACCAGGGCACUGCCCAGUGGGCUGAUCUUUCCUCCCAGUUCUACCUGCGGGAGGAGGACAUCGGUAAAAACCGGGCCGAGGUAUCACAGCCCCGCCUCGCUGAGCUCAACAGCUAUGUGCCUGUCACUGCCUACACUGGACCCCUCGUUGAGGACUUCCUUAGUGGUUUCCAGGUGGUGGUGCUCACCAACACCCCCCUGGAGGACCAGCUGCGAGUGGGUGAGUUCUGUCACAACCGUGGCAUCAAGCUGGUGGUGGCAGACACGCGGGGCCUGUUUGGGCAGCUCUUCUGUGACUUUGGAGAGGAAAUGAUCCUCACAGAUUCCAAUGGGGAGCAGCCACUCAGUGCUAUGGUUUCUAUGGUUACCAAGGACAACCCCGGUGUGGUUACCUGCCUGGAUGAGGCCCGACACGGGUUUGAGAGCGGGGACUUUGUCUCCUUUUCAGAAGUACAGGGCAUGGUUGAACUCAACGGAAAUCAGCCCAUGGAGAUCAAAGUCCUGGGUCCUUAUACCUUUAGCAUCUGUGACACCUCCAACUUCUCCGACUACAUCCGUGGAGGCAUCGUCAGUCAGGUCAAAGUACCUAAGAAGAUUAGCUUUAAAUCCUUGGUGGCCUCACUGGCAGAACCUGACUUUGUGGUGACGGACUUCGCCAAGUUUUCUCGCCCUGCCCAGCUGCACAUUGGCUUCCAGGCCCUGCACCAGUUCUGUGCUCAGCAUGGCCGGCCACCUCGGCCCCGCAAUGAGGAGGAUGCAGCAGAACUGGUAGCCUUAGCACAGGCUGUGAAUGCUCGAGCCCUGCCAGCAGUGCAGCAAAAUAACCUGGACGAGGACCUCAUCCGGAAGCUGGCAUAUGUGGCUGCUGGGGAUCUGGCACCCAUAAACGCCUUCAUUGGGGGCCUGGCUGCCCAGGAAGUCAUGAAGGCCUGCUCCGGGAAGUUCAUGCCCAUCAUGCAGUGGCUAUACUUUGAUGCCCUUGAGUGUCUCCCUGAGGACAAAGAGGUCCUCACAGAGGACAAGUGCCUCCAGCGCCAGAACCGUUAUGACGGGCAAGUGGCUGUGUUUGGCUCAGACCUGCAAGAGAAGCUGGGCAAGCAGAAGUAUUUCCUGGUGGGUGCGGGGGCCAUUGGCUGUGAGCUGCUCAAGAACUUUGCCAUGAUUGGGCUGGGCUGCGGGGAGGGUGGAGAAAUCAUCGUUACAGACAUGGACACCAUUGAGAAGUCAAAUCUGAAUCGACAGUUUCUUUUCCGGCCCUGGGAUGUCACGAAGUUAAAGUCUGACACGGCUGCUGCAGCUGUGCGCCAAAUGAAUCCACAUAUCCGGGUGACAAGCCACCAGAACCGUGUGGGUCCUGACACGGAGCGCAUCUAUGAUGACGAUUUUUUCCAAAACCUAGAUGGCGUGGCCAAUGCCCUGGACAACGUGGAUGCCCGCAUGUACAUGGACCGCCGCUGUGUCUACUACCGGAAGCCACUGCUGGAGUCAGGCACACUGGGCACCAAAGGCAAUGUGCAGGUGGUGAUCCCCUUCCUGACAGAGUCGUACAGUUCCAGCCAGGACCCACCUGAGAAGUCCAUCCCCAUCUGUACCCUGAAGAACUUCCCUAAUGCCAUCGAGCACACCCUGCAGUGGGCUCGGGAUGAGUUUGAAGGCCUCUUCAAGCAGCCAGCAGAAAAUGUCAACCAGUACCUCACAGACCCCAAGUUUGUGGAGCGAACACUGCGGCUGGCAGGCACUCAGCCCUUGGAGGUGCUGGAGGCUGUGCAGCGCAGCCUGGUGCUGCAGCGACCACAGACCUGGGCUGACUGCGUGACCUGGGCCUGCCACCACUGGCACACCCAGUACUCGAACAACAUCCGGCAGCUGCUGCACAACUUCCCUCCUGACCAGCUCACAAGCUCAGGAGCGCCGUUCUGGUCUGGGCCCAAACGCUGUCCACACCCGCUCACCUUUGAUGUCAACAAUCCCCUGCAUCUGGACUAUGUGAUGGCUGCUGCCAACCUGUUUGCCCAGACCUACGGGCUGACAGGCUCUCAGGACCGAGCUGCUGUGGCCACAUUCCUGCAGUCUGUGCAGGUCCCCGAAUUCACCCCCAAGUCUGGCGUCAAGAUCCAUGUUUCUGACCAGGAGCUGCAGAGCGCCAAUGCCUCUGUUGAUGACAGUCGUCUAGAGGAGCUCAAAGCCACUCUGCCCAGCCCAGACAAGCUCCCUGGAUUCAAGAUGUACCCCAUUGACUUUGAGAAGGAUGAUGACAGCAACUUUCAUAUGGAUUUCAUCGUGGCUGCAUCCAACCUCCGGGCAGAAAACUAUGACAUUCCUUCUGCAGACCGGCACAAGAGCAAGCUGAUUGCAGGGAAGAUCAUCCCAGCCAUUGCCACGACCACAGCAGCCGUGGUUGGCCUUGUGUGUCUGGAGCUGUACAAGGUUGUGCAGGGGCACCGACAGCUUGACUCCUACAAGAAUGGUUUCCUCAACUUGGCCCUGCCUUUCUUUGGUUUCUCUGAACCCCUUGCCGCACCACGUCACCAGUACUAUAACCAAGAGUGGACAUUGUGGGAUCGCUUUGAGGUACAAGGGCUGCAGCCUAAUGGUGAGGAGAUGACCCUCAAACAGUUCCUCGACUAUUUUAAGACAGAGCACAAAUUAGAGAUCACCAUGCUGUCCCAGGGCGUGUCCAUGCUCUAUUCCUUCUUCAUGCCAGCUGCCAAGCUCAAGGAACGGUUGGAUCAGCCGAUGACAGAGAUUGUGAGCCGUGUGUCGAAGCGAAAGCUGGGCCGCCACGUGCGGGCGCUGGUGCUUGAGCUGUGCUGUAACGACGAGAGCGGCGAGGAUGUCGAGGUUCCCUAUGUCCGAUACACCAUCCGCUGACCCCGUCUGCUCCUCUAGGCUGGCCCCUUGUCCACCCCUCUCCACACCCCUUCCAGCCCAGGGUUCCCAUUUGGCUUCUGGCAGUGGCCCAACUAGCCAAGUCUGGUGUUCCCUCAUCAUCCCCCUACCUGAACCCCUCUUGCCACUGCCUUCUACCUUGUUUGAAACCUGAAUCCUAAUAAAGAAUUAAUAACUCCCA